GCACCUCCUGACUACUCCCUGCGGGACGGCUGGGUGUGAGGGUGGCAGCCUUGUGCUCAAGCCGAGGCUGGGCUGGAGGAUGGAGAAGGACACGGGGACCACACACAGGAGGCACCGGCCCGGCCUCAGGGCCCUGCCCUCAGGAGUGGCCCUUGGGCACCUCAAGGCGGCCAGUGAGGCCUCUGAACUUCAGCGAAGCAGGAGUCUGGGAGGCCUGCAGCCCGAGGGGGACCCUCCCAGCCGCCCUAGGAAGCCUCACAAGGAGCUGGAGUCCGAAGAUCAAGGGAAAGACCCAAGCAGUAACGCGGAAGAUGCCAGCUGUCAGAAAAACCUAGCACAAGACAAGAAGGAAAGCUUCAGCACCCUUGGGAAGCUGGGUCAUGAGAGUGGAAAACAAGACCCAGAGAGGGAGAAGAGCGACUUGGAGGCCAGCAUGCAGGAGGUGCAGGAAGGCGAGCACGCAGACGGAGGCUUGCAGGAGGCCAAGGAACAGGAGGCAGAGUCCAUAAAGCUAAAUGACCUUCAGGAAGAAGAGAAAGCAUCUGUGUUUGUGGAGAUUGAUCUGGGAGACCAUGCUGAGGAGGUGGUCACCGAUGCCAAGAAGGAAGAGAAGCCGUCCCAGAUGGAUGUGGAAGAUCUGUCAGAAGACGAGAUGCAGACCAGCUGGGUGUGCUGCAUCCCGUACUCCACCAGGAAGAGGGCAAAGGAGAGCACCUAGCGCCCCGGAGAGGGUGCUCAGAGCUUGGCGAAGAAGAGGAAGGAGACGGGGUGCAGAGGGGCUGGGGGCACAGGAGGCGGGACGGAGGGCGAUCCGGCCACCUACUUGCCGCCCAAGAGCCUUCUCUGCCAGGCACUGAGGUUUCUGUUUUCUUCUUGUGGGACUGGCCAGGCCUGGAAGGAGCGAGAGCACAGACUGCGCCUUUGGGCUAAAGAUCCCGCCAGCUCUGAGCAACGCUGGGGUGCCGAUGACCACACCAGGUGUGAGCCACGCCUGAAACCCACUGCCCACUGGGUGAGUGAUGACGUGACCUUCAACAAACACAAUAAACAAGCACGGGAAGAUGCUCCUCCUCUCCACCAGAUGCUCCUCCUCUCCACCAGAUGCUCCUCCUCUCCACCAGAUGCUCCUCCUCUCCACCAGAUACUACUCCUCUCCACCAGAUACUACUCCUCCUCUCCACCAGAUGCUCCUCGUCUCCACCAGAUGCUCCUCCUCUCCACCGGAUGUUCCUCCUCUCGUCGAGAUGCUCCUCGUCUCCUCGAGAUGCUCCUCGUCUCCACCGGGUGCUCCUCGUCUCCACCGGAUGCUCCUUGUCUCCGCCGGAUGCUCCUCCUCUUCGCCAAAUACUACUCCUCCUCUCCGCCAGAUCCUACUCCUCCUCUCCGCCAGAUACUACUCCACCUCUCCGCCAGAUCCUACUCCUCCUCUCCGCCAGAUCCUACUCCUCUCUGCCAGAUCCUACUCCUCCUCUCCGCCAGAUCCUACUCCUCCUCUCUGCCAGAUCCUACUCCUCGUCUCCGCCAGAUGCUCCUCCUCGUCUCCGCCAGAUGCUCCUCGUCUCCGCGAGAUGCUCCUCCUCUCUGCGAGAUGCUCCUCCUCUCCACCGGAUGCUCCUCCUCUCCUCGAGAUGCUCCUCCUCUCCUCGAGAUGCUCCUCGUCUCCACCGGCUGCUCCUCGUCUCCGCCGGCUGCUCCUCGUCUCCGCCGGCUGCUCCUCGUCUCCGCCGGAUGCUCCUCCUCUCUGCCAGACACUACUCCUCGUCUCUGCCAGACACUACUCCUCCUCUCCGCCAGACACUACUCCUCGUCUCUGCCAGACACUACUCCUUGUCUCUGCCAGACACUACUCCUCGUCUCCGCCAGACACUACUCCUCGUCUCUGCCAGAUGCUCCUCCGCUCCACGAGAUGCUCCUCCUCUCCACGAGAUGCUCCUCCUCUCCACGAGAUGCUCCUCGUCUCCGCCAGAUGCUCCUCCGCUCCACGAGAUGCUCCUCGUCUCCGCCAGAUGCUCCUCCGCUCCUCGAGAUGCUCCUCCUCUCCACCGGAUGCUCCUCAUCUCCGCCGGAUGCUCCUCGUCACCGCCGGAUGCUCCUCGUCUCCGCCGGAUGCUCCUCCUCUCCGCCGGAUGCUCCUCCUCUCCACCAGAUACUACUCCUCCUCUCCACCAGAUACUACUCCUCUCUGCCAGAUACUACUCCUCUCCGCCAGAUACUACUCCUCCUCUCCGCCAGAUGCUCCUCGUCUCCGCCAGAUGCUCCUCGUCUCCACGGGAUGCUCCUCGUCUCCACGGGAUGCUCCUCCUCUCCACCAGAUGCUCCUCCUCUCCUCGAGAUGCUCCUCAUCUCCACCGGAUGCUCCUCGUCUCCACCAGCUGCUGCUCCUCUCCACCAGCUGCUCCUCAUCCCCACUGGAUGCUCCUCAUCCCCGCCGGAUGCUCCUCCUCUCCGCCAGAUCCUACUCCUCCUCUCCGCCAGAUCCUACUCCUCCUCUCUGCCAGAUCCUCCUCCUCGUCUCCGCCAGAUCCUCCUCCUCGUCUCCGCCAGAUCCUCCUCCUCGUCUCCGCCAGAUGCUCCUCCUCGUCUCCGCCAGAUGCUCCUCGUCUCUGCCAGAUGCUCCUCCUCCCCACGAGAUGCUCCUCAUCUCCACCGGAUGCUCCUCAUCUCCACCGGAUGCUCCUCGUCUCCACCAGCUGCUCCUCGUCUCCACCAGCUGGAGGACUCCAGCCCCUUCCUGCCCUGGCCUCUUGCUCAGUGGCUUGUUGGGUGGGGACAGAGGCCCCUGGGGCACAGCAGGGGAGGCUCAGCCCUUUGUGGGCCUCGUGUGAGCUGCAGCUCCUGGAAGCACCCCCACCAGGCAGGAGUGAGAGGUGCAGGGCAGGGAUGGAGCAUCUGCUGUGUCACCAAAGUCCCUGCAGGAGCCAGGAGCACGGUGGACGCAGCUGAGCCCCGGCUGUGACUGCGAGAGCAACAGAGACUGUGGUGCUGGCACUAGGAUCUGUCCCUGGAGGGAAGCCACAUGCUCCCCACUCAGAGGAGGAGAGGGAGUCUUCCUAGGGGUGUGGGGGGCUCCAGGACAUGCCUGUAAGACGAGUUUCACCAGAAUCCACCCAGAGCCCUCUCGUUCAGACACGCACACGUGCAUAUUCAUAUGUACACAGCACAUACAUGCUCGUACAUACCACACAUGUGCACAGGAGGGCACGGGCAGGUGACCUGCAGCAUCUCUGAUCCGGGUGUCUCUAAGGCAGUCAGAGGCCACAGGCGGAGAUGCUGUGUGCACUGUCUAUUCCCGUGGAGACACAUGGGGGCCGUCCCUGUGGUGCACAUGAUAAUGCAGAGGCUCCCAGAGGGUGAGCUCUGCCCAUCACUCAGCCAGGGAGGGAGGGGCCCUUUUCAGGGAGCCGCAUGCCACGCAGAGCUUGUCCCACUGGGUAGUUUCCUCUGAUCAAAGUGGGGCACCAUCCAGGCUGCAGAGAGAAAGGGGACCCCCCAAAGCCAGCACCCACCCUUGACUGAAAGACACCACAGAAGAUAAGUGCCCAUCGGCCCCAGAGUCAUCAUUUCCCAGACAACCGGAAAUGGGCCCUGGACGGGCUGUCCUGGACAGGCUGCCGGGCAGUUGGGUGUGACUCAGUUGCGGCCUCCAACUGUGCCAACCAGAAAGGCACCCAGAGAAGCUUCCGGAAAUACGGUUGGUUUGUCCCCUUGGUGGGGCAGGAGGCGGCAGCUCUGCCGGGUGGCUCCCAGCACCCUCCCCCACAGAGCAAACAUCGGCAUGAGUCUGUCCACCCGUGUAUUCGUCCUGUCGCCGCGUGUGGCUGGCCUCAUUCUGGGUAUGCUGGCGGCAGCCACCUCUAGGACAGGGAGGUCCCAUGGCUCUGCAGACACAGGAGCUUGGCAGUGGCUUAGCUGUUAGAAUGUGAGCCUUCCAGAGUCAGACGCGCCUUUGCCUUCUGUUGGGCUCUGAGCUCAUUUCCUCAAACCCAGGAUGGUGCCAUAUACGGAGAGAGGCAUAGGUUGUCUUACGAGAGUGGGGUCGCGUUGCACUGUGGCCCCUGCCAGGCCCUGUCCGGAGUGCUGAACACAGAGCAGCAGGUGCCGCCGGUCCCCAGCCUCUUGGAGCCCCGUUCCCUCUGGGCGUCGUAGACAGUCGAGUUCAGCACAUCUCUACGUGGAGUUUCGCAAAAAAGGCAACCACUUUGAAAUGGGAGGGCCGCAGCGCCAUGGCCUGGCGACGCCUGUGAGUGACUACAGUGGGGCCUGGAGGAGGAGCAGGGGGAUGAAUGCAGCCUUGGGGCAGGCGCUGGGGCCUGGAGGAGGCUUGGGGAGCAGGGCAUGGGGGGCGGGGAGCGAGUGCAGCCUUGGGGCAGGCGCUGGGGCCUGGGCCUGGCUGGGCCCCUCUAUGCCUUUCAGUCUUGAGGUCUGGAAACCCGGCCGGGAUCUCCCCCGAGUGGGCAGUGCUGUUGGUGGCGGCGGGGGGGAGUGGUGCUGGCACUGUGUGGCCGGGCAGAGCCGAGGCCAAAGCAGUUCCAUCCACACGCAGUCCACGAAGGGACGUCGGGCGCCUCCCACAAGCAAAGGCCCCGCCCGGCUCCAGCCCGGCCCGCAGGGACGACCUUGCCCUUCUUUCCUCCCUGGCCAACAGCACCACCCCGUGGGGGCCCCGGUGCUGAGGGCUCAGGCUGCCUGUUUCCGUCCUGGAAACCACAGACACCCGAGAUCCAAGCAAGGAAGGCAGGAUUUCCAUACCUCCUCCCCAGCUGAGCAUUCGCUGGAGGGGGACGGGGCUGUCACUACGUCCCUUAUGAUGAUCACCUCAUAGAGGCUGGGCCUCCCCACACCAGGACCACACGCCCAUGAGGGCCCCACAGGCCUCAGCCUAGAGAGCCCCCAUGGGAAACCCUGUGCUGUGAAUGGUGUGGAAAUUCCCCUGUGUCCUUCCCACGUGACCCCACAAAACCCUCAGCCGUGGACAUCCCGAGUUCCUCUGAACGCCCGGCCUUCCCAAGCCUCGCCAGCGCCACGGACAUCCCGGGGCCCCGGGGAAGGGUGGCUCUGCCGGGAGACAGGGUCUUCUCUCUGGCUCUGGUUCUGAAGGCUGUGGUGGGUGCAAGGUUCACCAGAGACGGCAGGACUCCCGUGCCCUGGAGCGGGAGGGAGUCUCUCCUGUGUCUCCCCUGGGCGCCGGCUCCUGCUGAACCCCAGACCCAGCUGUGGGAGAAAGCUGCCCAGGGCCCUGCAGGAGAGGCGGGGCCAGCCCUGGUGCACACAGGGGCAGAGGCACCUGGGCUGGUCUGGGCUGGGAGGUCAACUCUCCGUGUUGCAAUGCUGUGUCCAGGUCUGAAAAGGGCAAUGUGAAAGCAACUCCUCAGGGACAGAAGCCAGGCCACUCUGGGGAGAGGCAGGACACAGCCCUUCUGGCCCUGAACACCUUGAGGGGCAGGCAGGGGGUGAUGACCCCACUCUACAGAUGGGAGCACCGAGGUGCCCAAGGCAGGGGGUGAGGACCCCACUCUACAGAUGGGAGCAGUGAGGUCCCCAAGGUGGGGGUGAUGACCAUAUUCUCCAGAUGGGAGCACCGAGGUCUCUGAGGCAGGGGGUGAUGACCCCACUCUACAGAUGGGUGCAUUGAGGUCCCUCAGGCAAGAGUGAUGACCCCACUCUACAGAUGGGAGCACCGAGGUGCCCGAGGCAGGGGGCGAGGACCCCACUCUACAGAUGGGAGCACCGAGGUUCCCAAGGCAGGGGGUGAGGACCCCACUCUACAGAUGGGAGCAGUGAGGUCCCCAAGGUGGGGGUGAUGACCAUAUUCUCCAGAUGGGAGCACCGAGGUCUCUGAGGCAGGGGGUGAUGACCCCACUCUACAGAUGGGUGCAUUGAGGUCCCUCAGGCAAGAGUGAUGACCCCACUCUACAGAUGGGAGCACCGAGGUGCCCGAGGCAGGGGGCGAGGACCCCACUCUACAGAUGGAAGCACUGAGGUCCCCGAGGUGGGGGUGAUGACCGUAUUCUCCAGAUGGGAGCACUGAGGUCUUUGAGGCAGGGAGUGAGGACCCCACUCUACAGAUGGUUGCACUGAGGUCCCUCAAGCAAGAAUGAUGACCCCACUCUACAGAUGGGAGCACCAAGGUCCCCAAGGCAGGGGGCGAUGGGAGCACCAAGGUGCCUGAGACAUGAGUGAUGACCCCACUCCACAGAUGGGAGCACCGAGGUCCCUCUGUGGGCAGCUUGGGGCCAGGCACAGGACUGGCAGAGGCUGGGAGCACAGCUUGUCGGGGCAUCUGCGGGUGUGAGGGCCUGACACUGUCUUCAGGGCUUAGCCUUUGUUCUCCCUGCAAGAGGGGACAGAAUGCCCUUUGUCUUUGUAAAUCUAUGCCCUGCUUUAGGCAAAAAGAGGAAUCCGGAGAGCACUCCUGGACCUGUUUCUUCUUAAUCGUCUUCAUCUCAAAGGCCCUUCCUGUUUUGGGGAGUCACACACACUCUUCUGACACUGACGACCUGGAGUGUCACAGACCCUGAAGGUGAAGGGCUCUGUCCCACAAGACUCUGCCCCUACUUCUGAUGACAGCCGUACAUGGGUACCCAGGCAACCCACACUCACUCCUGACAACUGCAGAUUUGGGGAACUUUACAUCCCCUCAGAUUCACUAGAACACCUCCCAGGGCUCAGGAAAGUGCUUUACGUACAAUCAUGCUUAUUAUGAAGGAAACCCAUGAACAGCUCAGUGAAGAGAGUGGGGAGGUGGGCACUGAUCUCUGAGCACCGUGGGGGCUCCCCAGCCUGGGGGCUCCCCAACCCUGAUGCCCAAAAGUUUUUAUCUAGGCCUCAUUACACAGGUAUGAUUGAUUAAGUCAUUGGUCAUUGGUGAUUGAACACAAACUCAAUCUCUGGCCCCUCCCAGGAGUGGGGGCGGUGAGGGGGGCUGGAAGUUCCUCUCUAAUUACAUGGUUGGUUCCUCUGGCAACAAGCUCCCACCCUAAAGCUACCUUGGGGUCCCCCAAGAGUCACCUCAUUAGGGUAAACAAAUGUGGUGAAAAAGAGUUGUUAUGAAAUCAGACACCCCUAUCAGGAAAUUCCAAAGAUUUAAGGAGUUCUGUCCCUGGAACAGGGGACAAAGACCAGAUGUAUUUUUUAUUAUACCACAAUACAAAUCUCUUAAUUUAUUCAGGUCUCCUUCGAUUUAUCUCAGUAGCGUUUUGUAGUUUUAGGUGAUAAGCUCAUGCACACUGAGAUUCAAAGGGGUCUGUUGGAGCGUUCAGCAAUUCAUGAACUGAGCAGUACCAGAACGUGUGAGGUUCAGCGUGAGGUUCAGCGCUCCACUGAGGUUGAGGGGCGGAGCUCUUUUCUAAGUGUCUGCAGAAGCGGGACAAAGACAAGACAUCUGGUUAAAAGGAAGUCCCUGGUGAGAGGCUGGUUUGGCAGUUUCUGGGCAGUGUCAGUUUCGUGGCCCAGUUCCCAGUGGGCUUCGGUGUGCUCACACAGGGUCCCAGGCACUGAAGCCGCCUCAGCCCAGGGCCUCCUGGUUAACUUUCUCAUGUAGCUUUCCGAGUAUAUGUCCACCACUUGUUUUGGUCAAAGCCACUCAUAAGUAAUUUAACAUUUUUGAUGUCAAGAACAAUAAAUAGAAGUUUCCUCUUUGUGCCUCCCCAGUCACUGGGCUUCAGUCCCAGGAGGCAGGUGCCAGGCAGACGUUGGUCCCUUCUGCUAGUUUUGCCUGGUCUUGAACCGGUGCUGUGGGCUCUUCUGGGGCUGGUUCCUUUCAUGCUGAGUCAUGUCUAUGUGACUCCUCAGUAGUUAGUUUUUUAAAAAAUUGCCAGAUAUAAAUGUGUGCUCAGGCAGGUUUUUGAGAACUCCACACCAUCUCUUGGGAACGAUGAGAAGUCCCCUGAGUCCCUGUGGCAGGACGUGGGCUUUUCAUGGGUCAGCCUGAGCCCCGCUCCAUGGCCCCGAUGGGCGCUGGGGCAGCACCCUGGCUGGACAUGGGCUCCUAGAGAGGGCAGUCAGUGCUCGGCAGGCCAGAAUCAUGGAGGAGGGGUCGGGAAAGCACUGCUGACCCCCAAUCCCAUGGAUAUGCUGUCAUCCUCCCAAUGGCCUGGCUGAUGGGCCAUGGUGGGUGUGGACCCCUGAGUGAGUGUCUGGGGGGAAGUGUCACGGGGUCAGCCUGUGUGCUUCCUGGGCUCCUUGUCUACAUGGCUGCGCAUCUGCUUGGCUGUGUGUCCGGGACCUGCUUGUGUCCACUACAGGCCUGGGCCCAAGGAAUCUCGGGAGGUGGAAAUGGACACCCGGGGCCGCAGAAGCUGCACAGGUGGGGCCAAGAACCAACCAAGCCUUGCUGCCAGCUCCCCGCUCCACCCACUGUGAUGCCAGCUGCUUCUCACAUCUGUGAAGCCUCACCCAGCCUUGGGCCAUCAUUUCAGGUAAAUAAAAAGGCCUAAUGGCCCCAUCAGGCCCUGAGCUCCCUGCUUCCUGAGGAGCUGUCUUCUGCUGGAACUUGGAGGCCACGUGGGCAGAAUGAAACUCCUGCUUCCGACAGCAGACGGCAGCAGUGACCUACUCCUGGCUGCCCUGCCCAUCUGGAGCGGGUUCUGGGUCUUUUGGGCCCUUUGAGGUUGGUCCGCCCUCCUGCCCUGGCAGCAGCCAGUAUUUUACUCCCAGUUGCUCCAGCCUCCCCCAACCCCCUUCCCCGUAAGUAACCUGCCCCGACGCUUGUCCUGGAGCCACGGUGUGGAAGAUUCCAGCAGCAUUGAGGAACCAAAUUUUAUAUACAGCGUUUCCUCCAAGCACGCAGCUCUGAUGUGCCUUUUCCAGGGCCAAAGGCCCCUUCAGGAAUCUUCAGGCUUCCCGCUCCACCUCACCUUCUGUAGUGCUGCCAGGCUGACGACAGCCCCCGGGUCUGUGGCUGGCCCCUCUCUCCCAGAGCAUCUUGGCCUGCAGUGCUGGCCACAGCCAGAGAGAGGGAAGAGACAGCCCCAGCAGUAACCACGGGUGCCUUCGGCCCACGCACCUGCCGGUCGGCCCCAAGGGUGCCAGGCCUUCCUCUCCUAUCGCCGCUGUGGGGCUCCAAAGGGCAGCCAGGAGCCCCAGCUCUGCUGUGGCUUUGCUGUUCCCCAACUGUGAGACCCUCAGAGAGCUGCCGGGCGCAGGUUUCCUCCUCGGCCAGCGAGCAGUCAGACCAGGCUUCGGACCCCUCUACUGUUCCAGGGUGGAGGGGAGGACCCAGGAGACCCAAUGGCCUGGAUGCCAACAGCCAGCGUGGCCUGACGAUGCCAUAGGGCACAGGGACAGGCUCUCCGUCCUCUGCGGCCCCGUUCUGCUCCCACCCCAGUGCCCUCCUUUCACCCUGGGGUCCUCCCUGGACCAGCAGCUGCCACCCACAGCACACUGGGAUAUUUGUGCUGGCCUAGCUACUACCUGACACAGCUGACCACCUCACCCGGCUGACGACCCACACAGCCUCCUGGCCUGGGUCCUCCUGCGCCAGCAUUGUGUGUCAAGUGUGUGUGUGGCUGGCAUUCCUGUGUGCCGCGUGCAGAGCCUGCAGGACGCCCUUCAGUUCCCAGGAUGCCCCACCACAGAGGGGGACUGGUCCCCCCGAGGGUCCUGGGAAACCCUGUUCCAACCACAUGCCACAUAGGUCCUGUUACGUGAGUUAGAGGGGUGCGUGUGCUUCUCAAGAUGAGCUUUCAUCAAGUUCUUCCUCCACGCGACGUUGGUCCAAUUGGCCGGUGGGGAGUACAGUGCUAGGUGAGGGUCUCCGCUGGGGAGCUUGACACAGCGGGGCGCAAAUAAAGCCGUCACCAAUCCAAACCCGUUCUGCACUGAUACCUCGUACAAUAGCAAUAAAAAUGUGUCAGCAAGAACGCCAAA